CCCAGCCUCGGGCAAGGAAGAGACGCGACCAUGUGCGCAUGCCCCGAAUUUAUCACGGAGGGGCGGGGCUGAGGCUGCGGGAGCUGGAGCGGGGAAGAAAAGGGAAUUCCAACCUGUGGAACCUUGGGGGGUCCCCGGGGUCGGCGCCUUCCCAUUGACUGUGGGCGGUGCAAGGGACGGAGCCUCUGGCGGCUCGUGGGGGUGUUGGGGUCCGCAGGGGGAGGGAGGGGAGUGUCAGAGUGUGAGCGGGGUACGGGAAUUCCAAAUUUGAGGGCCUCCCGGCUCUGGCGCCGGGGAGGGAGAGCUCAGGCCGCCAUGCGGGACAGGACCCACGAGCUGAGACAGGGGGAUGACAGCUCGGACGAAGAGGACAAGGAGCGGGUCGCGCUGGUGGUGCACCCGGGCACGGCACGGCUGGGGAGCCCGGACGAGGAGUUCUUCCACAAGGUCCGGACAAUUCGGCAGACUAUUGUCAAACUGGGGAAUAAAGUCCAGGAGUUGGAGAAACAGCAGGUCACCAUCCUGGCCACGCCCCUUCCCGAGGAGAGUGAGUGAAACCCCGGCUGCAGGGCGCAUGCUCCGCCCCAGGGAUUGUGGGGGUUGUAGUUCCACGCAGGUGGUGGCCAGAGUGGUUUGUUGAGGUGGGGGCUGCUGUUUGGGAGUCUUGGCCUUCUCUUAUUCAGGCAUGAAGCAGGAGCUGCAGAACCUGCGCGAUGAGAUCAAACAGCUGGGGAGGGAGAUCCGCCUGCAGCUGAAGGCCAUAGAGCCCCAGAAGGAGGAAGCUGAUGAGAACUAUAACUCCGUCAACACAAGAAUGAGAAAAACCCAGCAUGGGGUCCUGUCCCAGCAAUUCGUGGAGCUCAUCAACAAGUGCAAUUCAAUGCAGUCCGAAUACCGGGAGAAGAACGUGGAGCGGAUUCGGAGGCAGCUGAAGAUCACCAAUGCUGGGAUGGUGUCUGAUGAGGAGUUGGAGCAGAUGCUGGACAGUGGGCAAAGCGAGGUGUUUGUGUCCAAUAUCCUGAAGGACACGCAGGUGACUCGACAGGCCUUAAAUGAGAUCUCGGCCCGGCACAGUGAGAUCCAGCAGCUUGAACGCAGUAUUCGUGAGCUGCACGACAUAUUCACUUUUCUGGCUACCGAAGUGGAGAUGCAGGGGGAGAUGAUCAAUCGGAUUGAGAAGAACAUCCUGAGCUCAGCGGACUACGUGGAACGUGGGCAGGAGCACGUCAAGACGGCCCUGGAGAACCAGAAGAAGGCGAGGAAGAAGAAAGUCUUGAUUGCCAUCUGUGUGUCCAUCACCGUCGUCCUCCUAGCAGUCAUCAUUGGCGUCACAGUGGUUGGAUAAUGUCGCACAUUGUUGGCACUAGGAGCACCAGGAACCCAGGGCCUGGCCUUCUCUCCCAGCAGCCUGGGGGGCAGGGCAGAGCCUCCAGUCGGACCCCUUCCUCACACUGGCCCCUAUGCAGAAGGGCAGACAGUUCUUCUGGGGUUGGCAGCUGCUCAUUCAUGAUGGCCUCCUCCUUCAGGCCUCAAUGCCUGGGGGAGGCCUGCACUGUCCUGAUUGGCCGGGACACACGGUUUUGUAAAAAAUUAAAAAACAAAAAAAGAGCAUAGAAA